GCAAACGGCGGGACCAGCAGCGACGGUAGCAGCAGCAUGGCCGCGAUCUAUGGGGGUGUAGAGGGGUGAGUGCGGCCCGGCGGAGGGAGCCUGGGCCCGAAGGCGGGGCGGAAGGCCGUGGCCAGCCUGGCAAGCUGGUGGCCUUGAUCCUCGGCGUCCGGGCACUUUGGGCGGCGGGACCUUGCGGUGAAGAGGGGAGGCACACGAUCCGAGGUCCUUUUAGUCUCAGAGGAUGGGAAGAUCCUGGCAGAAGCAGAUGGACUGAGCACAAACCACUGGCUGAUCGGGACAGACAAGUGUGUGGAGAGGAUCAAUGAGAUGGUGAACAGGGCCAAACGGAAAGCAGGGGUGGAUCCUCUGGUACCGCUGCGAAGCUUGGGCCUAUCUCUGAGCGGUGGGGACCAGGAGGACGCGGGGAGGAUCCUGAUCGAGGAGCUGAGGGACCGAUUUCCCUACCUGAGUGAAAGCUACUUAAUCACCACCGAUGCCGCCGGCUCCAUCGCCACAGCUACACCGGAUGGUGGAGUUGUGCUCAUAUCUGGAACAGGCUCCAACUGCAGGCUCAUCAACCCUGAUGGCUCCGAGAGUGGCUGCGGCGGCUGGGGCCAUAUGAUGGGUGAUGAGGGUUCAGCCUACUGGAUCGCACACCAAGCAGUGAAAAUAGUGUUUGACUCCAUUGACAACCUAGAGGCGGCUCCUCAUGAUAUCGGCUACGUCAAACAGGCCAUGUUCCACUAUUUCCAGGUGCCAGAUCGGCUAGGGAUACUCACUCACCUGUAUAGGGACUUUGAUAAAUGCAGGUUUGCUGGGUUUUGCCGGAAAAUUGCAGAAGGUGCUCAGCAGGGAGACCCCCUUUCCCGCUAUAUCUUCAGGAAGGCUGGGGAGAUGCUGGGCAGACACAUCGUAGCAGUGUUGCCCGAGAUUGACCCGGUCUUGUUCCAGGGCAAGAUUGGACUCCCCAUCCUGUGCGUGGGCUCUGUGUGGAAGAGCUGGGAGCUGCUGAAGGAAGGUUUUCUUCUGGCGCUGACCCAGGGCAGAGAGAUCCAGGCUCAGAACUUCUUCUCCAGCUUCACCCUGAUGAAGCUGAGGCACUCCUCCGCUCUGGGUGGGGCCAGCCUAGGGGCCAGGCACAUCGGGCACCUCCUCCCCAUGGACUAUAGCGCCAAUGCCAUUGCCUUCUAUUCCUACACCUUUUCCUAGGGGGCUGGUCCCGGCUCCACCCCCUCCAAGCUCAGUGGACACUGGGUCUGAAAGGAAGGAGUCUUUUGCUUCCUUUCUCCUUUUUACAAAAACAAACAUAGAAGAAAAUAAAUGCACUUUAUCCACUCCCCAAUUGGACUGCAUUAUCAAACACAUGUGCUAUGUACAUCCUCAGUGCACCUGCCAGCAGAUAUCCUGGAGGGCUCAUGAGUGAAUUUAGUCCAAGAUUUAAAGCCCUGCCCCCAGGUGCUCAGCCUGUGAUCUGUAUCCACUCAGCAUGCACUUGGGCAGAUGAUUUGUCUGUGUGCUACCCUUCCCCCCAUAUUACCAUACAUAUGCACUGUGUGGCUGCCAGUUAAUCUGUGACCUGUUUUCUCCUGUCGUGUCAAGUGGGUAACGAUCCCUGGCGACCACAGUCAGCAGAAACAAGUGCUCACCAUUCAGAACAUCACAGGGAGUAACCUUAGGUAUAUCACACCCUCUCCUGAGACUCCCAGCAAGAUUUAGGGGCUAGAGUACAAUUCUAGACUGGGAGCAUCUUUACCUCACUGGAUUUAGUAACUGCAGGUAAGCAGGACAUUUUGAAGUUUUUCCUAUGAAUGAGUUUUUGAAAGGUUAUGAGGAUGGCUGAGAUCCAAGAAGACCAACUAGGUACCGCUCACCUCGGUAGCUGACCUAUUCCUGGCUACUACUAGCCUGGCUCUGCUUACAGCGUGACACUAUGUGUUGUGUGUUCCUGGGAAUGAGGAGCAUCAGUGAAGAGCAGACAUGAUUCCUGCCCUCUGGGUACCAUAGUUCAGCCAGUGAAGGCAAACCUGAAGCUUCGGUUCCACAGCCUGUGCUGCUUGGUGAAGACUAAGGACAGGAGUCUCGAUCCACAAUAGCUGCCUCUCCAGGUGUUUUAUUAGAGGCAUGUGGAUCAUGUCCUGCACAUCAGUUCUCCAACUUACAGACAUCAGUUAUUCUAGAGUUUGUUUUAAAACACGGUUUUGGCCGGGCACGGUGGCUCACGCCUGUAAUCCCAGCACUUUGGGAGGCCGAGGCAGGUGGAUCACGAGGUCAGGAGAUUGAGACCAUCCUGGCUAACACGGUGAAACUCCAUCUCUACUAAAAAAUACAAAAAAUUAACCGGGCGUGGUGUCGCGCGCCUGUAGUCCCAGCUACUGGGGAGGCUGAGGCAGGAGAAUGGCAUGAACCCAGGAGGUGGAGCUUGCAGUGAGCCGAGGUCGCACCACUGCACUCCAGCCUGGGCGACAGAGCGAGACUCUGCCUCAAAAAAUAAUAAAUAAAAAUAAAAUCA